CAGGUAAAAAUCCAGGGGCAGAACAAGGAGAUGUUGGCGGCCGCCUGUCAGAUGUUCCUGGGGAAGACGGAGGCUGAGAUUGCCCACAUUGCCCUGGAGACGUUAGAGGGCCACCAGAGGGCCAUCAUGGCCCACAUGACUGUGGAGGAGAUCUAUAAGGACAGGCAGAAAUUCUCAGAACAGGUUUUCAAAGUGGCCUCCUCAGACCUGGUCAACAUGGGCAUCAGUGUGGUUAGCUACACUCUGAAGGACAUUCACGAUGACCAGGACUAUUUGCACUCUUUGGGGAAGGCUCGAACAGCUCAAGUCCAAAAAGAUGCACGGAUUGGAGAAGCAGAGGCCAAGAGAGAUGCUGGGAUCCGGGAAGCUAAAGCCAAGCAGGAAAAGGUGUCUGCUCAGUACCUGAGUGAGAUCGAGAUGGCCAAGGCACAGAGAGAUUACGAACUGAAGAAGGCCGCCUAUGACAUCGAGGUCAACACCCGCCGAGCACAGGCUGACCUGGCCUAUCAGCUUCAGGUGGCCAAGACUAAGCAGCAGAUUGAGGAGCAGCGGGUGCAGGUGCAGGUGGUGGAGCGGGCCCAGCAGGUGGCAGUGCAGGAGCAGGAGAUCGCCCGGCGGGAGAAGGAGCUGGAGGCCCGGGUGCGGAAGCCAGCGGAAGCGGAGCGCUACAAGCUGGAGCGCCUAGCCGAGGCAGAGAAGUCCCAACUAAUUAUGCAGGCGGAGGCAGAAGCCGCGUCUGUGCGGAUGCGUGGGGAAGCUGAGGCCUUUGCCAUAGGGGCCCGAGCCCGAGCCGAGGCUGAGCAGAUGGCCAAGAAGGCAGAAGCCUUCCAGCUGUACCAAGAGGCUGCUCAGCUGGACAUGCUGCUAGAGAAGCUGCCCCAGGUGGCAGAGGAGAUCAGUGGUCCCUUGACUUCAGCCAAUAAGAUCACACUGGUGUCCAGCGGCAGUGGGACCAUGGGGGCAGCCAAAGUGACUGGGGAAGUACUGGACAUUCUAACUCGCCUGCCAGAGAGUGUGGAAAGACUCACAGGCGUGAGCAUCUCCCAGGUGAAUCACAAGCCUUUGAGAACAGCCUGAGCCUUCAGCCCUCACAGAUGCCCAGCCUCAUAGCUGAAGUUGCCUGAAUGAUCCUCCUGUUGCAUGUAACCCACUGGCCUCCCUGAGCAUGUCCAUUGACAGUGAGGUCCCACCCCUCAUCUCUCCUUGCCAAAUAGUUUGUGCCUUGUCUUGAAGGGGGUUGCUCCCCUUGCCAACCUCACACUGCUAUGAUUGCCAACUCCAGCGGUCCCAUGUCAGCCUUCUGAUGAUCCCACUCCACCCCACCUCAACUUAUUUAACUUCCUAAUUAAAUCAGACUGUUUGAGCCUGUUGUCUAGAAUAUUUUCCUGACCAAGACUGAGGGAUGGGCUGGAGGUUUUCAACUUUGCUACCCAAAUAAAUUGCUGUAAGUAAGUACUAAUAAAACAGAAGCAACUGGAAAUUAA